AGACACCAAGAGCCGCGGCAGCAGAGAGGAGCGCUGAAACAUGGCUGAAGCGGCCACGGGCUUUCUGGAGCAGCUCAAGUCCUGCAUAGUUUGGUCUUGGACGUAUCUGUGGACCGUGUGGUUCUUCAUCGUGCUAUUCCUGGUCUACAUCCUGCGGGUGCCUUUGAAAAUCAACGACAACUUGAGCACAGUGAGCAUGUUUUUGAACACAUUAACACCGAAGUUCUACGUGGCCCUAACAGGCACUUCCUCACUAAUAUCAGGGCUUAUUUUGAUAUUUGAAUGGUGGUAUUUUCGCAAAUACGGAACUUCAUUCAUUGAACAAGUCUCAGUAAGCCACUUGCGCCCCCUUCUGGGAGGGGUUGACAACAACUCUUCCAACAAUUCUAAUUCCAGUAACGGGGACUCAGAUUCCAAUAGGCAAAGUGUCUCAGAAUGCAAAGUAUGGCGAAAUCCACUAAAUUUAUUUAGGGGUGCUGAAUACAAUCGGUAUACUUGGGUGACAGGACGAGAGCCUCUUACUUACUAUGACAUGAAUCUCUCUGCCCAAGACCACCAGACAUUCUUUACUUGUGACUCGGACCAUCUGCGUCCCGCAGAUGCAAUAAUGCAGAAAGCCUGGAGAGAGAGAAACCCCCAAGCUAGGAUUUCUGCAGCUCAUGAAGCCUUGGAGAUAAAUGAAAUUAGGUCCAGAGUUGAAGUUCCCCUAAUUGCUUCCUCUACCAUCUGGGAGAUAAAAUUGUUACCAAAGUGUGCAACUGCUUAUAUUCUCUUGGCUGAAGAGGAAGCAACAACCAUUGCUGAAGCAGAAAAAUUAUUUAAGCAGGCCCUGAAGGCUGGAGAUGGCUGUUACCGACGCUCUCAGCAGCUACAACAUCAUGGAUCCCAGUAUGAAGCCCAACAUAGACGAGACACCAAUGUCUUGGUGUACAUCAAAAGAAGGCUAGCAAUGUGUGCCAGAAGACUCGGGAGGACCAGGGAAGCAGUGAAAAUGAUGAGAGAUUUAAUGAAGGAGUUCCCCCUUCUGAGUAUGUUCAAUAUCCAUGAAAACCUUUUAGAAGCCCUUCUGGAACUACAAGCAUAUGCUGAUGUUCAGGCAGUCUUAGCAAAGUAUGAUGAUAUAAGCUUACCAAAGUCAGCAACAAUAUGCUACACAGCUGCUUUGCUCAAAGCAAGAGCUGUCUCUGACAAAUUCUCUCCUGAGGCUGCAUCUCGGCGGGGGCUGAGCACAGCAGAGAUGAAUGCAGUAGAGGCCAUUCAUAGAGCUGUGGAAUUCAAUCCUCAUGUGCCAAAAUACCUACUAGAAAUGAAAAGCUUAAUCCUACCCCCAGAACAUAUCCUGAAGAGAGGAGACAGUGAAGCAAUAGCAUAUGCAUUCUUUCAUCUUGCACACUGGAAGAGAGUGGAAGGGGCUUUGAAUCUUUUGCAUUGUACGUGGGAAGGCACUUUUCGGAUGAUCCCUUAUCCCUUGGAAAAGGGGCACCUAUUUUAUCCUUACCCAAUCUGUACAGAAACAGCAGACCGAGAGCUGCUUCCAUCUUUCCAUGAAGUCUCAGUUUACCCAAAGAAGGAGCUUCCCUUCUUUAUUCUCUUUACUGCUGGAUUAUGUUCCUUCACAGCCAUGCUGGCCCUCCUGACACAUCAGUUCCCGGAACUUAUGGGGGUCUUCGCAAAAGCUAUGAUUGACAUUUUCUGCUCGGCAGAGUUCAGGGACUGGAAUUGCAAGAGUAUUUUCAUGCGUGUUGAAGAUGAACUGGAAAUCCCUCCGGCACCUCAAUCUCAACAUUUCCAAAACUGAACUCAUCACCCCUCUUCCCCCACCACCAAAACUGCUCCUCCUCCUGUAUUCCUGACCUCCGCCAUCCACCCCGUUGCUCAAGCCGGAAACUCGGCAGCCCUUCCAAACUCUUCCCUCUCUCACUCCCCACAUCCCAUCGUCUCGGCCUUCACAAUCUGUCAGUUCUAACCUCCUAAGCAACUAGGCCUUCAGUAAAUGUGAUUCACCUCUUCUUUCCCUCCUUUUCCCAAAGCAUCCCUCUUAGUCUAGGUCCUUGUUGUUUCUUGCCUGAACUCCUGCCAUAGUCUUAACUGGUCUCCUUGCUUCCUGUCUUAUCCUCCACCGUCUUUCUUUUAUACUGACACAAGAAUGGUCUUUCUGAAUUGCACAUGUGAGCAUGUCACUUCCCUGCUUAAAUUUCUCCAGUGGAUUCCCAGGGACUUCAGGAUCAAGUCCUAGUUGUUCAGCAUGGCAUCCAAGACUCUUUAUGAUCUGGCCCUUGCUUACCUCUCAGCCUUAGCUCUCCCAACUCUUGCACAGUCACUGCUCUUCAGCCAUAGUGGAUCACUCACCAUUCCCAGAUGUACCAGGCUCUCGCACACCUCUGCACCUUUGCACGUGCUGUUUGCUGUGCGUGGAAUGCCCUUCACUGUCACCACCCUGCUCAUCCACUCUACUAAUGCCUCUUCAUUCUUUUAUACUCAGCUUUCUUUAAAGUUCUUCUAAGCUGAGUUAGGUGUCUGUCCUUUAUGAUCCCGCAGUAUUCCAUGAAUACGUAUAUUCUCACAUUUAUUGUACUGUAUUAUAAUUGUUGAAAACUUGUCUGUCCCAUUUAGAAUGUGAGCUCCUUGAGAGCAGAACGGUGUCUUCAUUAUCUCUGUAUCCCCAAGGCUUUGCACAGUGCCUUGCUCAUAGUAGGUUUUCAAUAAAUGAUUAUUAAAUAAAUAA